GUAGUGCGAGUGGGGCGGACGCGCGCAGCCCGCCCGCCCGGCGACCAGCAAGGAGUUGGCAUCCUUUGGAAGAGUUCGUGAAAGCUUUCUGCCCAGAGCUCCUGGACCAAUGCAUCUUCCCACCACCUUAAACCACUGAGCAGUUCAGAGCCCCAGUUGCAGACGACUUGUCCUGCCACCACCAUGAGUUCUGAAUGUGAUGGUGGUUCCAAAGCUGUGAUGAAUGGCUUGGCACCUGGCAGCAAUGGGCAAGACAAAGACAUGGAUCUUACAAAAAUCUGCACUGGGAAGGGAGCGGUGACUCUCCGGGCCUCGUCUUCCUACAGGGAAACCCCAAGCAGUAGCCCUGCGAGCCCUCAGGAAACCCGGCAACACGAAAGCAAACCAGGUCUGGAGCCAGAGCCUUCUUCAGCAGAUGAGUGGAGGCUUUCUUCCAGUGCUGAUGCCAAUGGAAAUGCCCAGCCCUCUUCACUCGCUGCCAAGGGCUACAGAAGUGUGCAUCCCAACCUUCCUUCUGACAAGUCCCAGGAUUCCAGUCCUCUACUAAAUGAAGUUUCUUCUUCCCUUAUUGGAACUGAUUCCCAAGCCUUUCCAUCAGUUAGCAAGCCUUCAUCCGCCUAUCCCUCCACAACGAUUGUCAAUCCUACUAUUGUGCUCUUGCAACACAAUCGAGAACAGCAAAAACGACUCAGUAGCCUUUCAGAUCCUGUCUCAGAAAGAAGAGUGGGAGAGCAGGACUCAGCACCAACCCAGGAAAAACCCACCUCACCUGGCAAGGCUAUUGAAAAAAGAGCAAAGGAUGACAGUAGGCGGGUGGUGAAGAGCACUCAGGACUUAAGCGAUGUUUCCAUGGAUGAAGUGGGCAUCCCACUCCGGAACACUGAGAGAUCAAAAGACUGGUACAAGACUAUGUUUAAACAGAUCCACAAACUGAACAGAGAUGAUGAUUCAGAUCUGUACUCUCCCAGAUACUCAUUUUCUGAAGACACAAAAUCUCCCCUUUCUGUGCCUCGCUCAAAAAGUGAGAUGAGCUACAUUGAUGGUGAGAAGGUAGUCAAGAGGUCGGCCACACUACCCCUCCCAGCCCGCUCUUCCUCACUGAAGUCAAGCUCAGAAAGAAAUGACUGGGAACCCCCAGAUAAGAAAGUAGACACAAGAAAAUAUCGUGCAGAGCCCAAGAGCAUUUACGAAUAUCAGCCUGGCAAGUCUUCCGUUCUGACCAACGAAAAGAUGAGUCGGGAUAUAAGCCCAGAAGAGAUAGAUUUAAAGAAUGAACCUUGGUAUAAAUUCUUUUCGGAAUUGGAGUUUGGGAAACCGCCUCCCAAAAAGAUAUGGGAUUAUACUCCUGGAGACUGCUCUAUCCUUCCUAGAGAGGAUAGAAAGACUAAUCUAGACAAAGAUCUCAGCCUCUGCCAGACAGAGUUAGAGGCAGAUUUAGAAAAAAUGGAGACGCUUAAUAAAGCACCCAGUGCAAACGUGCCACAGAGCUCAGCCAUCAGCCCUACUCCGGAAAUUUCUUCAGAGACUCCUGGAUAUAUAUAUUCUUCCAACUUCCAUGCAGUGAAGAGGGAAUCAGACGGGGCUCCUGGGGAUCUCACUAGCUUGGAGAAUGAGAGACAAAUUUAUAAAAGUGUCUUGGAAGGUGGUGACAUCCCUCUUCAGGGCCUGAGUGGGCUCAAGCGACCAUCCAGCUCUGCUUCCACUAAAGUGGAUCGUAAAGGUGGGAAUGCUCACAUGAUUUCUUCAUCUUCAGUCCAUAGCCGAACGUUUAACACUAGCAAUGCGUUAGGCCCUGUGUGUAAGCACAAGAAGCCCCUGUCAGCUGCGAAGGCCUGCAUUUCGGAAAUCCUUCCAUCCAAAUUCAAACCCAGGCUCUCUGCUCCCAGCGCUCUUUUGCAGGAACAGAAGAGUAUCCUCUUGCCCUCAGAGAAGGCUCAAAGCUGUGAGAACCUUUGUGUUUCUGGUUCUUUAAAUGAUUCCAAAAGAGGCCUCCCCCUCCAAGUGGGAGGGAGCAUUGAGAACCUGCUCAUGCGCUCCCGACGGGAUUAUGACAGCAAGUCGAGCAGUACCAUGAGCCUCCAGGAGUACAGCACCAGCGGCAGGAGGCCCUGUCCUCUCUCAAGAAAGGCUGGGAUGCAGUUCACCAUGCUUUAUCGGGACAUGCACCAGAUCAACCGAUCUGGCCUCUUCCUGGGCUCCAUCUCCUCCUCCUCGAGUGUGCGGGAUCUUGCCUCCCACUUUGAAAAGAGUAGCCUGGCAUUGUCCAGGGGUGAGCUGGGCCCCAGCCAGGAGGGCUCGGAACACAUCCCCAAGCACACCGUCUCUUCCCGCAUCACCGCUUUUGAGCAGCUGAUUCAGCGGUCCCGUUCCAUGCCAUCCCUGGACCUGUCCGGAAGGCUGAGCAAGUCUCCCACACCUGUGCUGUCCCGGGGCAGCCUGACCUCAGCCCGCUCGGCCGAGUCCCUACUUGAGUCAACCAAGCUCCAUCCCAAGGAGAUGGAUGGGAUGAACUCCAGUGGGGUCUAUGCUUCCCCAACAUGUAGCAAUAUGGCACACCAUGCCUUGAGCUUCAGGGGCCUUGUGCCUUCUGAGCCUCUCUCCACCUGCUCUGAUGACGUGGACCGCUGUUCAAAUAUCUCCACUGACAGCAGAGAAGGCAGUGGCGGCAGUGUUCAUGGAGAUUUCCCCAAACAUCGCCUCAACAAGUGCAAGGGCACCUGCCCGGCCUCAUACACCCGCUUCACCACCAUCCGGAAGCAUGAGCAGCAGCAGACCUCUAGACAGCCUGAGUGGCGCCUGGAUGCCAGAGGGGACAAGAGCACCCUCCUCAGGAACAUCUACCUAAUGAGCCCCCUUCCUUUCCGGCUGAAAAAGCCCCUCCACCACCACCCCAGACAACCUUCCCCUGGUGACUCCUCAGGCCUCCUGGUGGGCCAGAAGCCAGACCUCCCCAGUCAGCCCCAUCAGGACCAGCCCCCUUCUGGGGGGAAGCCCGUGGUUCCCACACGCCUGUCUUCCCGACACACCAUGGCCAGGCUUAGCCGCAGCUCAGAGCCCUCUCAGGAGAGACCCACGGCCCUGGAGGACUACCCAAGGGCCAUUAAUAAUGGAAACUCCGUGCCAUACUCAGACCACAGCCUGGACAGGAACAACAACCCACAAAGUGAACUGGCACCAUCCCGUGGAGAUUCAGAAUCGCCAAGACAUUUUAUACCAGCUGAUUACUUGGAAUCCACGGAAGAAUUUAUUCGAAGACGUCAUGAUGAUAAAGAGAAACUUUUAGCGGACCAGAGACGACUUAAACGCGAGCAAGAAGAGGCUGAUAUUGCAGCUCGACGCCACACAGGCGUCAUUCCGACGCACCAUCAGUUUAUCACUAAUGAGCGCUUUGGGGACCUCCUCAAUAUAGACGAUACUGCAAAAAGGAAAUCUGGGUCAGAGAUGAGACCUGCCAGAGCCAAAUUUGACUUUAAAGCUCAGACACUAAAGGAGCUUCCUCUGCAGAAGGGAGAUAUUGUUUACAUUUAUAAGCAAAUUGAUCAGAACUGGUAUGAAGGAGAACACCACGGCCGGGUGGGAAUCUUCCCACGCACCUACAUCGAGCUUCUUCCUCCUGCUGAGAAGGCACAGCCCAAAAAGUUGACACCAGUGCAGGUUUUGGAAUAUGGAGAAGCUAUUGCUAAGUUUAACUUUAAUGGUGAUACACAAGUAGAAAUGUCCUUCAGAAAGGGUGAGAGGAUCACACUGCUCCGGCAGGUAGAUGAGAACUGGUACGAAGGGAGGAUCCCGGGGACAUCCCGACAAGGCAUCUUCCCCAUCACCUACGUGGAUGUGAUCAAGCGACCACUGGUGAAAAACCCUGUGGAUUACAUGGACCUGCCUUUCUCCUCCUCCCCAAGUCGCAGUGCCACUGCAAGCCCACAGUUUUCCAGUCACAGCAAGCUCAUCACGCCAGCCCCCUCAUCUCUGCCCCACUCCCGCCGAGCCCUGUCCCCCGAGAUGCACGCUGUCACCUCUGAGUGGAUCUCACUGACUGUGGGGGUCCCAGGCAGGCGUUCUCUGGCCCUGACCCCACCCUUGCCUCCUCUGCCAGAGGCUUCUAUCUAUAACACUGACCACCUCGCCUUGUCACCAAGGGCCAGUCCCUCCCUGUCUCUCAGCCUCCCCCAUUUGAGUUGGUCAGAUCGUCCCACCCCACGAUCAGUAGCUUCUCCACUGGCCCUACCUUCCCCACACAAAACCUACUCCCUAGCACCUACUUCCCAGGCCUCCCUUCACAUGAAUGGAGACGGUGGUGUCCACACGCCAUCUUCAGGCAUCCACCAAGAUAGCUUCUUGCAGCUGCCGCUGGGGAGCUCUGAUAGUGUCAUCUCCCAGCUUAGUGAUGCCUUUAGCAGCCAGAGCAAGAGGCAGCCAUGGCGCGAAGAGAGUGGACAAUAUGAGAGGAAAGCAGAGAGGGGGGCAGGCGAAAGAGGCCCUGGUGGACCCAAGAUCUCUAAGAAGAGCUGCUUGAAGCCUUCAGACGUGGUCAGGUGCCUGAGUACUGAACAGAGACUCUCAGAUCUCAACACCCCUGAGGAGAGCCGGCCCGGCAAGCCCCUGGGUAGCGCUUUUCCAGGAAGUGAGGCUGAGCAGACAGAGCGGCAUAGAGGUGGCGAGCAGGCGGGGAGGAAAGCUGCUCGGAGAGGUGGGAGCCAGGAAGCGGUUUGCAAUGAGAUCAUAAACAUUGCCGAAAAAUCUGUUCAUUACUGCAGCACUGUUUCUCAUCCCCUUGACUUUCAUCACAAGGUAUCCCCUUCUGACAAUAAAUCAUCUUUAAUCAUUUCUCAGCAACCUCAAGCCCAGCAGCGAAGAGUCACCCCCGACAGGAGUCAAACCUCACAAGAUUUAUUUAGCUAUCAAGCAUUAUAUAGCUAUAUACCACAGAAUGAUGAUGAGUUGGAACUCCGCGAUGGAGAUAUCGUUGAUGUCAUGGAAAAAUGUGACGAUGGAUGGUUUGUUGGUACUUCAAGAAGGACAAAGCAGUUUGGUACUUUUCCAGGCAACUAUGUAAAACCUUUGUAUCUAUAAGAAGACUGAAAACCAUGGAGAUUAUUUUUAUUGGAGGAGGAAGCAUCAUUCAUGAACCGAUCUUUUUAGUUGAGUCAGUAGGAAAAUUAAUACAGUGGAUAAAGUAAGAAGCAAAAGACAGGGACAGAGAAGUGUUGUGUUUAAAACCCAAGCCUGUCUAAGGUUACUGUGUAUUAGACAGGGCCGAACUAGUGUGCUGAGCAAAAAGAAUUGAAGCAAAUUGUAUUUACUUAGCCGCUUCUGGGAGCCACUUCAGCCUUUCCCCUCCCCUCCACUUCUUGGGUAAUCUGACCUGAAGCAUAGUCCAGGAGCAGAGUUAGCCAGAAAUGCCUCCUGCUGCCCCAGCCUUAGAGAGCUCCCAUCUCAAUCAUUGAGCCUGAAGGCUUCAAGCCCAAGAAUGCAACAAGACCCCCAGCCUACAUUUCUCAGCUCCCCUGGAGCCAGCUGAUCCUGUAACGCUGCUGGAGGUCAGUCUGAGCUACCAAGACUGUCCCUAGACAAAGGUGGAGUCCCCCACACUGCCCAAGACCAAAUCCCUCACUCAACCUGCUGAGGUGUGGAUGGGGAAACAGAGGCAAAACUGAGGCACCUGAUGCAUUCAGCCUGCUGUGCAGCAGUGCCAUUGACUGCCCUGAUGUUCAGAGAGAAACGCACACAAGGUUUGCCCAUGAGAAUUGGGGAGCAGAUGGCCAAGCAGAUAGGUUAUGUCUGUUUUCUGAGUGAUGAAGUCAGGAAGCCCUGUGGCUCUGGAGGCCACUUGUGGUUCAUUCUUUUCCCAUAUCCUUGGCUUUUAGAAAUGGUUACCUUCAGGACAGUGCAGCUGCAUUUAUCAGAGCACUAUUGCUAAGUUUUCUUUUCUGGCUUGUGUUUUUCUGGGACAGUUUAGAAUUGGGAGGCCUAUUCUCAUAGAACACCAAAAAUGAUGUUCAGUGAUUCAUUUAACAUACACCAAUGUACUCUGGCUGCUGGGGGGACAACCAUAAGCAAGACAUGCCCAGGGUUUGCCGUGGCUCCAGAUCUACUCCCUGUAGGAGUUCAAGGAUCACACAAACGGUAGUAACCAGGGUUGUGAAUCUGAGUACACCCUGGCAAGGCUUCUCUUCAGACUGAAGCAGCAAUUCUGCCACUACCAGCAGCAACCAGGACGUCUGUUCUUUGUGGGGGCCAGAUCAGAAGAGAGAGGCCCCUGUGACGCCCGGGCUGCUUGGUCACAACUCUGUCCAAUUCAAGGAUGUUUAUCGGCCUCUCUUAGAUCCUGAGUGAGACAAAUACAGAAAUGACCCAUUCCCUGCCCACCAGAAACUCAGAGGUGAUUGGGGAGACUGACACAGGAAAAUGAACUUAAUCAAGAGAGACUGUGAUAUGUGCUAAGAAGGGUGUGAGGGAGGGAGAGAUGAAUUUUCCCUGGAGGGAUCCUAGAAAGCAUUGUCAUAUUGCCAUCUCCAUUAGCUCACUUUUAAACAACUAGGGUGCUGGAAGAACCUUUGUCUGAGGGUAGUUCAUAGCUGGAAAUACUUGGAAUAUUUUCCAGAGUCUCUAAACUCUCAUCUUCCCCCACAGAUACACAUCCAAGCUCACAAAUAGGAGUAGCAAUUCUAGGUGGUAGGGUUGUGUACGGAACCCCUGGCUGUCUGCAUAUAUCUCAGAAUUACCCCAGGACCAUUGUCCCAAAGUCUAGAGUCUUUACAGGUAGGCAAAAUUUGUUUUCAAUGCCUGUGCCUCAGCUGCUGUCACAAAUACCCAUCUUAGGAUCCCAUCAGCUUCCCAUCCCCCACCAGACAGCCACAGUACCCUCACUUUCUCCCUAUUGUUCUUUCAAAUCCUGUUCUCAGGAAAGAAACUGCCACUAAUUCAUUCACACUAAGGUGUAAAUGAUUGAUAAUAGGAAUGAGUUACCUCUUCCCACAGACAUUUGUUUUUAAGUAUGACAGAGCAGGGCCUUAAUCCCAAGGGAAAAGGUUAUGGAACUGGAGGGGGUGAGCUUUCUGGGUAGAAGGAGACUUCCUGAAUUUCCUUAAAACCCAGUAAGAGUAAGACCUGUUGUUUUGGAAGGUCUGCUCCACCAUCUAAGAGCACUGUUUUUUUUUUUUUGUUGUUGUUGUUGUUUUACGGUCUCUGAGGGAAUAUAGUAAAAAUGCAUAUGCACGUGCAAUUUGCACGGCAGCAUUUCACCGAUUGUGGACUGUAUUGGCUAAUGUGUUUCCUGGUCUUUAGAUGCAAACCAUUAAUAACACUAUCUUAUCUCAUAGUUUUUUCAGGGGUGCUUCUUGAUUAGUAGGGAAUUUUGAACACCUCUUUAAAUACAGCUAGAAAAUAAAACCAAUUUGUAAAGCCACAUUUGCAUAUGAUGCCAGCCUCACGCAUUUGUAUAUCUCCAGAAAUUCAGGUAUGCCUCACCAAUUUGCCCGUCUUUAAUAAAAUCUUGUGUUAAAAUUUGCAUCACGUCGCCUUCCUAUGUAUGACGAAACAAGAAACAGAGAUUUCCAAUUGCUCUUUUGUCUUCAGACAUUUAGUAAUAUAAAGUACCUAUUUUUAUGCUGAAAUGUUUAUACAGGUUUAUUAAUAGCAAGUGCAACUAACUGGCGGCAUGCCUUGCAACACAUUUUGAUAUAUUAGCCAUGCUUCCGGGUAAAGGCAAGCCCCAAACUCCUUAUCUUUUGCAGUCUCUCUGGGAUCAGUAAAAGAAAAAAAAAAUAAUGUGCUUAAGAAGUGGGACUGUAAAUAUGUAUAUUUAACUUUGUAUAGCCCAUGUACCUACCUUGUAUAGAAAAAUAAUUUUAAAAAUUUGAAUGGAAGGGGGUAAAGGAAGUCAUGAAGUUUUUUUGCAUUUUUAUUUAAAUGAAGGAAUUCCAAAUAACUCACCUACAGAUUUUUAGCACAAAAAUAGCCAUUGUAAAGUGUUAAAAUUUACGAUAAGUAUUCUAUUGGGGAGGAAAGGUAACUCUGAUCUCAGUUACAGUUUUUUUUUCCUUUUUAAUUUCAUUAUUUUGGGUUUUUGGUUUUUGCAGUCCUAUUUAUCUGCAGUCGUAUUAAGUCCUAUUGCUAGAAUAGGUUACUACAAAAAAGGUUAUAUUCUGAAAGAAAAAUAACUGACAUUAUAUAUAACCAAUUAAUUUAAAGUAUUGCCAUUUAAAUUACACACUGAGAGCAUGUCCUAUGCAGACAUAGAUUUUUCUGUUCAUUUAUUUUUCUUCAUUGCAGUGGAUUGAUUUGAUAAAUAGAUGUGUUGAAUUACUACAUUUGCUGUACAUAUUAUUUAAUAAACUUUAUUCAGAAUUGCGUGGCA